AGAGUGUCGCUUUCAGUUGUAACGGACUUCAUCACAUCACAAAUUGUACUCGUUCUCAUCCUUUUAAGAAAGUUCAGACCCAGGAAAAUUUCCAUAGUACCUUAAUGAAAAAGAUAGAAAUCAGUGGGACGUGUCUUUCCUUUCAUCUCCUUUUCGGCUUGGAAAUCAGAAUGAGAAGGAUUGUUUUUGCUGGUGUUAUCUUAUUCCGCCUCUUAGGUGUUAUCUUAUUCCGCCUCUUAGGUGUUAUCUUAUUCGGCCGCUUAGGUGACCUGGGAACCUGCCAGACAAAACCUGGUCAGUACUGGAAAGAAGAGGUCCACAUUCAAGAUGUUGGAGGUUUGAUUUGCAGAGCAUGCAAUCUUUCACUGCCCUUCCAUGGAUGUCUUUUAGACCUGGGAACCUGCCAGGCAGAACCUGGUCAGUACUGUAAAGAAGAGGUCCACAUUCAAGGUGGCAUUCAAUGGUAUUCAGUCAAAGGCUGCACAAAGAACACAUCAGAGUGCUUCAAGAGUACUCUCGUCAAGAGAAUUCUGCAACUGCAUGAACUUGUAACUACUCACUGCUGCAAUCAUUCUUUGUGCAAUUUCUGAGUCAGUGGCCCAUAUCUAAAAUGCUUGGCAGAUCAAUCAGUCUCGAAGCCUGACCUGGCUAUCACAAAAUGAUGGCUAUUGUCAAUUAGCCCACUUCAGAAACCUCAGACCCUUGUAGGUAGAAGGAAUUUUGAUCUGAAAUUGACUUUGGUUUUCAAUAUUCCCAAUAUCUCCCCCACCACCUCCAACUCAUCUGAGAAAUAGCCCUUUCAACACCAUUUCUCUCCUCUCCUCCUUCUGCUUAAUUUACCUUCCUACCACAAGGCUACAAAGAAGGAAAAAUGUUAGUGAUUCUCCAAGUCAAACUAGGCAUGUCACCUCUAACUACUUUCAUUUCCCUCAAUAAUUCCAUACUCCAAAAUAUGGUUACAAAUGUUUCACAAGACAGCAAGUGACCUGAGAAUAUUCAUUUGGUUUCCAAAGCAAACUGCCUUGCUCCUUUGGGGUGAUUUAUGGUAUAGAAGAAACUGACUUAACAUAUACUAUAGGGAAAAAAUAAGCCAUGAAUCAGCAAGCCAGGCCUGCGGGAAAAGUAUGAACCCAAACAGGAAAGGGCUGAGGCAGGUGGUAGGGCUGGCACUUAUUUCUUCCAUCUGCCUCAGAGUUUAUCCAAAUUUUGAAUUUUCCGUACCUUAACCAUGCCUAAAUGCUUUGGCUUGUUCAAUUUUGGCAGAUUAAGCAGUUCAAGGUAAGCAGAGAAGUAAGUUCCCAACCACAAGGAAUUUAAAAGGAGUAGGAACGUACUUUGAACUACAUUUCCCAUUUUGCGAUCAUUACGUCUUCUAUUACAAUGCCCUACUUUGGCAGCAUGAAGAGUACUGCAUUAAUUUAAUUUAAUUUAAAAUUUAAUUUAAAACUGUCUUUCUCUGUAUUUUCAGGAGUUUGAAAAUUCAAAAAAUAAAUAAUAAAUGUCAAUAAAA